AACUGAAAAUCCACAAGACAGAAUAGCCAGAUCUCAGAGGAGCCUGGCUAAGCAAAACCCUGCAGAACGGCUGCCUAAUUUACAGCAACCAUGAGGUUCUUUACCACAGAGAAAAAGCAGGACCCACAAGAAUGUGAAAGCCUCAGUCUUGCAGCCUCUCUGAUGUCUUGUGGGUAAUACAGUGGAGAUGUGGUAGGAAAAGCUCACAGCCUUCCUCCAUAGGCUUCUGGUCUCACUUUCUGCACUGCUGGCCUCUUACAACAGGUUUUCGCAAUCAGGCUGAGCUUAAGAUAAACAGAUUGCCUCCUCCCUGGAAAAUCUAGGCUCUUGUACAAAUGGUGAUGAUCAUCAGGUCAAGGAUAGUCUGGAGCAAUUGAGAUGUCACUUUACAUGGGAGUUAUCCAUUGAUGACGAUGAAAUGCCUGAUUUAGAAAACAGAGUCUUGGAUCAGAUUGAAUUCCUAGACACCAAAUACAGUGUGGGAAUACACAACCUACUAGCCUAUGUGAAACACCUGAAAGGCCAGAAUGAGGAAGCCCUGAAGAGCUUAAAAGAAGCUGAAAACUUAAUGCAGGAAGAACAUGACAACCAAGCAAAUGUGAGGAGUCUGGUGACCUGGGGCAACUUUGCCUGGAUGUAUUACCACAUGGGCAGACUGGCAGAAGCCCAGACUUACCUGGACAAGGUGGAGAACAUUUGCAAGAAGCUUUCAAAUCCCUUCCGCUAUAGAAUGGAGUGUCCAGAAAUAGACUGUGAGGAAGGAUGGGCCUUGCUGAAGUGUGGAGGAAAAAAUUAUGAACGGGCCAAGGCCUGCUUUGAAAAGGUGCUUGAAGUGGACCCUGAAAACCCUGAAUCCAGCGCUGGGUAUGCGAUCUCUGCCUAUCGCCUGGAUGGCUUUAAAUUAGCCACAAAAAAUCACAAGCCAUUUUCUUUGCUUCCCCUAAGGCAGGCUGUCCGCUUAAAUCCAGACAAUGGAUAUAUUAAGGUUCUCCUUGCCCUGAAGCUUCAGGAUGAAGGACAGGAAGCUGAAGGAGAAAAGUACAUUGAAGAAGCUCUAGCCAACAUGUCCUCACAGACCUAUGUCUUUCGAUAUGCAGCCAAGUUUUACCGAAGAAAAGGCUCUGUGGAUAAAGCUCUUGAGUUAUUAAAAAAGGCCUUGCAGGAAACACCCACUUCUGUCUUACUGCAUCACCAGAUAGGGCUUUGCUACAAGGCACAAAUGAUCCAAAUCAAGGAGGCUACAAAAGGGCAGCCUAGAGGGCAGAACAGAGAAAAGCUAGACAAAAUGAUAAGAUCAGCCAUAUUUCAUUUUGAAUCUGCAGUGGAAAAAAAGCCCACAUUUGAGGUGGCUCAUCUAGACCUGGCAAGAAUGUAUAUAGAAGCAGGCAAUCACAGAAAAGCUGAAGAGAAUUUUCAAAAAUUGUUAUGCAUGAAACCAGUGGUAGAAGAAACAAUGCAAGACAUACAUUUCCACUAUGGUCGGUUUCAGGAAUUUCAAAAGAAAUCUGACGUCAAUGCAAUUAUCCAUUAUUUAAAAGCUAUAAAAAUAGAACAGGCAUCAUUAACAAGGGAUAAAAGUAUCAAUUCUUUGAAGAAAUUGGUUUUAAGGAAACUUCGGAGAAAGGCAUUAGAUCUGGAAAGCUUGAGCCUCCUUGGGUUCGUCUACAAAUUGGAAGGAAAUAUGAAUGAAGCCCUGGAGUACUAUGAGCGGGCCCUGAGACUGGCUGCUGACUUUGAGAACUCUGUGAGACAAGGUCCUUAGGCACCCAGAUAUCAGCCACUUUCACAUUUCAUUUCAUUUUAUGCUAACAUUUACUAAUCAUCUUUUCUGCUUACUGUUUUCAGAAACAUUAUAAUUCACUGUAAUGAUGUAAUUCUUGAAUAAUAAAUCUGACAAAAUAUUAGUUGUGUUCAACAAUUAGUGAAACAGAAUGUGUGUAUGCAUGUAAGAAAGAGAAAUCAUUUGUAUGAGUGCUAUGUAGUAGAGAAAAAAUGUUAGUUAACUUUGUAGGAAAUAAAACAUUGGACUUACACUAAAUGUUUAAUUCAUUCAUUUUAUUGUGAAAUAAAAAUAAAAUCCUUAGCUCCUCCACCAACUGAACAGACCCUCUUGGCCAAGGAGACCCCAGAAACCUUAAAAACUAAGUUUCCCAACCAUGACAAGAUGAGAGAUCAUUCACACCUCAUUAUAUUCCCUCCCUUGCUAACUGCCAUUGGACUUUUUCCACUGAGUUAAACAGAAACCCAUGGAAAACAAAGAACAGAAGACUCACUCCUUGGCUGACUUCACCUAGCUCACUCCACGUAGCGCCACAGCCAGACUCCCCUCCCCUCUUGCGGUUUCCACAUGACAACUGAUCAGCCUUCCCUCCUGAUAAGUGACCACUGCCCACAGACUGGUUCUGGCCAGUCCAUGGAGGCUGCACACAGGGUGCCUCUAUGUCCUUUGUUUCACCUUUUGAUAUAGAAAGGCUAAUUUUGCUGUAUUUUAAUGUUAAGUCUCCACCACAGAGUGAACACAGAAUGCAUGUGACAUACAUGUUUACAUACCACUAUUGUGUGACUGCCCCUCAUGAAUAUUCAUAGCCCCCCAUAACCUGUUAACUAUGUGUGUCUAGCCAAUCCACCAACCAUAAAACUUCUGUAAUACCCUCCCUUCCUCCAAGAGCCUGCUUUUGGUUGCUGUGGUAGGCUCUGCUUCCCAGGCUGCAGGUUGCAGGAGAGGAGGCUGCAGUGGCUCACGCCUGUAAUCUCAGCACUUCGAUGGGACGAGGCAGGCAGAUCACCUGAACCCAGGAGUUCGAGAGCAGCCUUGGCAAUGGCAAAACCAACCGUCUCUACAAAAAAUGCAAAAACUUAGCUGGGUGUGGUGGCAUGCACCUGUAGCUUCAGUUCCAGCUACUCAGGAGGCUGAGGUGAGUGGACUGCUGGAGCCAGGGAGUUCGAGGCUGCAGUGUCGAGAUCUUGCCACUGCACUCCAUUCUGGAUGAUAGAACGAGACCCCAUCUCAAAAAAAAAAAAAGUUCUCUCCAAUUGUAUAUAGCUUGUGAUUUUAUGUCAACACUAUCAAUAAAUAGCUUUCAGUGCAAGAAACCAAAAAUACUGUAAUAAACAGGCACAUAUUCUUCCCAAACCUCAUGCAGUUUACAAUCUAGUGAGAGACACAGAUAGCAGUACAGAGUCAAUUAAAGGUUAGUUUUCUUCAUGAAGAUGUUUUAAUUUUAAUUCAAUGUGAAAGGGUUCCAAGGAGUUUAUCUUGUUUUAUGCCAUUUUAUUUGAAGCACUACUUACUAAGUCAUUUGCUGAUAUUAAUCUAGUUAAAUCAAGAAAUAUUACAUGAAAAUGUUGCUAAAUCAGAGAUCAUGGGUAACAAUCACCUUUGAUUAUGAAUAAUCAUAUUUUAUUGAAAGGCAAGGCACAACAAAUAAUAAGAAGGAAAAAAUAAAUAAGCAAUGUUAUUGAUCUUUCAUUCUGUAUAUGUUUUGGGGGGAAUAUACUAGUUUCUUUUAGUGGCUGUAACAAAUUACCACAAACUUGGUGACUUAAAAUUUCACAGAUUUACUCUUUCUUACAGUUCUGGAGGUCAGAAGUCUGAAAUGGGUUUCAAUGAGCCAAAGUCAAGGUAUUGAUGACGCUACACUCCUCCGGAGGCUCUAGGCAGAUAGCCUUUUCCAGCUUCCAGAGGCUGCCUGAAUUCUUUCAUCCAUCUUAAAAACCAACAGUGUAGUAGCCUCAAAUCUCUCUCUCUGCUUCCUUCUUCACAUCUCCUUCUCUCCUCUGACUCUUUUGCCUCUUUCUUCUAAGGACGCACCAGGUCCACCUGCAUAAUCCAGAAUAAUUGCCCCAUCCGCAAAUCCUUAAUUUAAUAACAUCUGCAAAGUCCCUUUUGCUAUGUAAAGUAGCAUGUUCACAGGUUCUGGAGACUUGGCCAUGGAUACGAUUGCGGGGGGGGCAUUAUUCUUACCACAGAGCACCCCAAGAAAAUCUCCAAAUUUUGGGCUUCCAAUCCAUUUUGCUUCAAUUAUUUAAUAUUUUUACUCCUUCCAGUAGAUACUGAUUUCAUCCAUUGCCCUUAAGAAGGUAGGACAGAGAUUAUGGCACAUCUCACAUUAAAUGCUAUAUUUUCGUUGGAAAUACAUUUUUUGCUUCAACUUUUAUUUUAAAUUCAAGGGUACAUGUGCAGGAUGUUCAGGUUUGUUACACAGGUAAACGUGUGCCAUGGCGGUUUGCUGAACAGAUCAUCCCAUCACCAACAGAUCAUCCCAUUGAGAGGUGAAGCCGGCUGGGCUUCUGGGUUGGGUGGGGACUUGGAGAACUUUUCUGUCUAGCUAAAGUAUUGUAAAAUGGACCAGUCAACACUCUGUAAAAUGGACCAAUCAGCUCUCUGUAAAAUGGACCAAUCAGCAGGAUGUGGGUGGGGCCAAGUAAGGGAAUAAAAGCAGGCCACCCGAGCUGGCAGCGGCAACCCGCUCGGGUCCCCUUCCAUGCUGUGGAAGUUUUGUUCUUUCGCUCUUUCAAUAAAUCUUGCUGCUGCUCA